AUCUACGGGGCGGCAGGAGGCCCGAAGCAAGAUGGCGGUGAAUCAGAGCCACACCGAGAACCGCCGCGGAGCCCUCAUCCCUAACGGUGAAAGUCUCUUGAAGCGGUCUCCGAAUGUGGAGCUCUCCUUCCCACAGCGAUCAGAAGGCUCAAAUGUCUUUAGUGGUAGAAAGACAGGAACAUUGUUUCUCACUUCAUACCGGGUGAUUUUCAUAACUUCAUGCUCCAUCAGUGAUCCCAUGUUGUCUUUUAUGAUGCCAUUUGAUCUGAUGACGAACCUCACUGUUGAACAACCAGUAUUUGCUGCAAACUUCAUUAAGGGAACUAUUCAGGCAGCUCCAUAUGGUGGCUGGGAAGGACAAGCUACUUUUAAAUUAGUCUUCAGAAAUGGAGAUGCCAUUGAAUUUGCCCAGUUGAUGGUGAAAGCUGCCUCUGCUGCUGCCCGAGGAUUUCCACUUAGAACCUUAAAUGACUGGUUCAGCUCUAUGGGAAUUUAUGUAAUUACUGGGGAAGGGAAUAUGUGCACUCCACAGAUGCCUUGUUCAGUUAUUGUCUAUGGAGCCCCACCUGCAGGAUAUGGAGCCCCACCUCCCGGAUACGGAGCCCCACCUGCAGGAUAUGGAGCCCAACCCGUAGGAAAUGAAGGCCCGCCUGUGGGAUACAGAGCCUCACCUGUGCGAUAUGGAGCCCCACCUCUUGGAUACGGAGCCCCACCUGCAGGAUAUGGAGCCCCACCUCUAGGAUAUGGAGCCCCACCUCUUGGAUAUGGAACCCCACCUCUCGGAUAUGGAGCCCCACCUCUCGGAUAUGGAGCCCCACCUGCAGGAAAUGAAGGCCCGCCUGCGGGAUACAGAGCCUCACCUGCUGGAUCAGGAGCCAGGCCUCAGGAAUCUACAGCAGCCCAGGCUCCUGAAAACGAGGCUUCUCUUCCCUCUGCCUCCUCUUCUCAGGUCCAUUCUUAACCUUCUAAGAUGUAAACCUUGAAGACUCACCAAGCAAAGAGGUACCCUAAAAUUGAAGUCAGGAUAAGGAGGACGACUCAGGUAUGUGAUCACAGGCUUCUCGCAGGUAGUUGUUCCACCCUUUGGAAGGGCAAUCUUAUGGGGGAAGGUGAAACUUUACUUCUGUGCCUAGAUUUUAGAAGCAGAAUCAACUCUUAAAUAGCUGGCUAAAGGAAGAAUACCAUUGUGGGGCUAAUUCCCCAGUAAUUUGGUUGACAUUGGGUUGCAUUUUUAAACAUAACUUUUUCCACACUCGCAUUCAAGGUUCCUGUCUUCCCAUCCUCAUUCAAGAAACAUUUAUUAUGCUCCGUUUGCUAGGCACUAAGAUGCGUGCUAAAAACGUCAUGUUGAACACUUAGUUGUUUGAGAAAGCUAAAUUUUCAAUAGUAAGAGUGUUAUAAAUUACGGUGGAUCCACAAAAUGGAGUAUUAUACACCUGUUGAAAACUAUGUCUAGAGGUAGAGAAAGCCUUCUUUGAGGAGACCAAAACCAACAAAUAAAAGCAUGAUAAAUUGACUAUAUCAAAAUUUAAAACUUCUCUAUGACAGAAGUUAAAAGAUAGGCAACAGAAUAGGAAAAAGUGAUUUUCAACAUAUAUAUUAAUUUAUAGUCAGAAUACGUGAAUAACUACAAAUCAAUUCUCCCCAAAAUGACAGAAAUAUGAAUUGCCGAAUAACCAAGGCAAUAGCAUGGCCAGAAAACGUUUGAAAAGAUGUUCAGCUUGACUAGUGUUAGGGAAAUGCAACCUGAGAUGAGAAAACAUUUUUAUCUCCAAAGAUUUACAAAUAUUAAAACUCUUGAUAUGGCACUUUCACAUUUUAAAAUAUGCCUGCGAGAAAACUUGCAUGUGUGCACAAAGAUGCAUGUGGGAAGAUUUCAUUAUAUUCAUUGUUUCUAACAGCACAAAAUUAGAAAUAACCUAUAUGUCCAUUAAUAGGAAAUAUAUGAAUAGGCUAUGGUAUGCCCAUACUACGUAUGCAGAAAUUUCUAAGACUUGUUGAUAAGGAGAAAAGCAAGUUGUAGGGAGCAUAUACUAUAGUGAUUUUCAGCCUCAUCAGACUGAAUGCCCCAUUUUAUAACAAAUAUUUAUAUUUUAUAACAAACGUUUAUAUUUGUAUAUUUAUAACAAAUAUUUUGUAAUGUCUCCUUCACUUCAAUGAAGUUUGUAGAUAAUUGCAUAUGAUUCCACACCAUUUCAACCAAAAUUAAUAGGCCAUAAAUGUGAUAGAGGAAAUAAAAGGAGUUUGUAGUAAAA